ACAGCGGCCCUGCGGCUGGCGCGGCGGACGGGAUGAGGCGCUGCAGUCUCUGCGCUUUCGACGCCGCCCGGGGGCCCAGGCGGCUGAUGCGUGUGGGCCUCGCGCUGAUCUUGGUGGGCCACGUGAACCUGCUGCUGGGGGCCGUGCUGCAUGGCACCGUCCUGCGGCACGUGGCCAAUCCCCGCGGCGCUGUCACGCCGGAGUACACCGUAGCCAAUGUCAUCUCUGUCGGCUCGGGGCUGCUGAGCGUUUCCGUGGGACUUGUGGCCCUCCUGGCGUCCAGGAACCUUCUUCGCCCUCCACUGCACUGGGUCCUGCUGGCACUAGCUCUGGUGAACCUGCUCUUGUCCGUUGCCUGCUCCCUGGGCCUCCUUCUUGCUGUGUCACUCACUGUGGCCAACGGUGGCCGCCGCCUUAUUGCUGACUGCCACCCAGGACUGCUGGAUCCUCUGGUACCACUGGAUGAGGGGCCGGGACAUACUGACUGCCCCUUUGACCCCACAAGAAUCUAUGAUACAGCCUUGGCUCUCUGGAUCCCUUCUUUGCUCAUGUCUGCAGGGGAGGCUGCUCUAUCUGGUUACUGCUGUGUGGCUGCACUCACUCUACGUGGAGUUGGGCCCUGCAGGAAGGACGGACUUCAGGGGCAGCUAGAGGAAAUGACAGAGCUUGAAUCUCCUAAAUGUAAAAGGCAGGAAAAUGAGCAGCUACUGGAUCAAAAUCAAGAAAUCCGGGCAUCACAGAGAAGUUGGGUUUAGGACAGGUAAUGGGCCUUGAAGGUGGUGGCCCGGGUAAGAGCGGGGACAAGGAAGUGCUCUUAGAACUGGGUCUAGGUCUUGCCAUGCUGCUUUCCCCUCUGACCUGGGUUGGUUCUCCCCUCUGUCCAGCAGGUGCUGUUCCGAGACUCAGUCCUAAAGGGUUUUUUUUCCCACUAAGCAAGGGGCCCUGACCUCGGGAUGAGAUAACAAAUUGUAAUAAAGUAACUUCUCUUUUCUUCUA